GGCGCCACCGUUCCCAUCCAGGCUUGUCGGCGGCCACCGGCGGACCGGGCUUCGAGAUGGCCUCCCCGCCGCGGUGCUCCCCGACAGCCCAUGACAGGGAAUGCAAGUUGCCGCCACCCUCCGCCCCCGCCAGCGAGUAUUGUCCCGGCAAGCUGUCCUGGGGGACCAUGGCGAGGGCCUUAGGCCGCUUCAAGCUGUCGAUCCCGCACACGCACCUGCUGGCCACCCUCGACCCCCUGGCCUUGGACAGGGAACCACCACCGCAUCUGUUGCCUGAGAAGCACCAGGUGCCGGAGAAAUUGAUCUGGGGCGACCAGGACCCUCUCUCCAAGAUCCCAUUUAAAAUUCUGAGUGGGCACGAGCACGCUGUGAGCACCUGCCACUUCUGUGUGGAUGACACAAAGCUCCUCAGUGGCUCCUAUGACUGCACUGUGAAGCUGUGGGAUCCGGUGGACGGUUCUGUGGUUCGCGAUUUUGAGCACAGGCCCAAAGCUCCUGUUGUAGAGUGCAGCAUCACCGGCGACAGCAGCAGAGUCAUUGCCGCAUCCUAUGAUAAGACAGUGAGGGCCUGGGACCUGGAGACAGGCAAGCUGCUGUGGAAGGUCAGGUAUGAUACCUUCAUCGUCUCCUGUAAGUUUUCUCCUGAUGGUAAAUACGUGGUCUCAGGCUUCGACGUGGAUCAUGGAAUCUGCAUAAUGGACGCCGAGAACAUCACCACCGUUUCCGUCAUCAAAGAUCAUCACACAAGGUCCAUCACGUCAUGCUGCUUUGACCCCGACAGCCAGAGGGUGGCUUCUGUCUCAUUGGACAGGUGCAUCAAGAUCUGGGAUGUUACAUCCCAGGCCACGCUGCUCACCAUCACUAAGGCACAUUCCAAUGCAAUCUCAAACUGCUGUUUUACCUUCAGUGGCCAUUUCCUGUGUACAAGCUCCUGGGAUAAAAACUUAAAAAUAUGGAACGUCCACACAGGGGAGUUUCGAAACUGUGGAGCCUGUGUGACUCUGAUGCAGGGCCAUGAAGGUUCUGUCAGUUCCUGUCACUUUGCCAGAGACAGCUCUUUUCUCAUUUCUGGAGGGUUUGAUAGGACUGUGGCUAUUUGGGAUGUAGCAGAAGGCUACCGGAAGCUCUCUUUGAAGGGCCAUAAUGACUGGGUGAUGGAUGUUGCCAUUAGCAACAACAAGAAAUGGAUCCUGUCUGCUUCCAAGGAUAGGACCAUGAGACUGUGGAAUAUUGAAGAAAUUGAUGAAAUUCCUUUGGUAAUCAAGUACAAAAAGGCCGUGGGCUUAAAGUUGAAACAGAGACGGGGUUUCACCAUGUUGGCCAGGUUGGUCUCGAACUCCUGAGCUCAAGUGAUCCGCCCGCCUCAGCCUCCCAAAGUGCUGGGACUACAGGCGCAAGCUAUCCGCACCCAAACUGGGAUCUAAUCUAUUUCUUGCAAAAAAGGAAAAGAAAGAGGCCUACCUGAAGCUGAAGCAAGGAUGAGCCUGCUGCAUUUGACUUGCUCUGAAUCAAUCAACAUGAGAAGCCUGAGGCCAGGCUUCCCCGAGGCCUGCCCCAGGUAGGGUUUACCCCCCUCUCCAGCAGGCCUCAGUGUCCUGGAGUGGGCAGAACAGCAAAGCCCAGGGGCUGGGAGAGCCAGGGCAGGGGCGCGGCCACCUUGCAGGCUCUUCUCCAGGGGACCAUGCAUGGUGGGAACCCCUGAGGGGCCUCUGCCCAUGGCCUAGGAGACCUCAUCCCAUGGCACUCUUGCUUGUUAGUGGGAAGCAGACGUGAUGGGUGAGCUGUGCCAUUUGUUUUCAGUGUACUCUGUGAGCUUUGGCCAGAAACAGGCUCAGGGACGCAGGAGGGCACCUAGCACCUGCAUCAAUCUGCUUCACACCCCUGCUUUGUUCAGAAAUCUUGCCUACUUGCGUCUCAUGGUUCUGUAAAAGUUGGGUGUUCUCAGGAUGUCAGGGAGUCAUCCUCUUAGUCCCACAAUUUUACUCGGCACAGAACAAUGGAUGGGGCGGGACACUCACCCCCAUCCUCCCAACUGUCAAGGGGCUUGCCACGCAUGUCCUCAGGACCCCCAUGGCAGGAGACAUGAGCUGGCAGGAGACAUGAGCUGGCAGGAGACAUGAGCUGGCAGGACCUGCUUAGCCAUUGGUGGGGAAGCAGCCUGUGCUCAUUCUCUCUGCAAUUUCCGCCUUUGUGGGGUUAGAGAUUCCAGAGAGGGGCUGCGCCCAGUGGCUCACGCCUGUAAUCCCAGCACUCUGGGCUGCCAAGGUGGGUGGAUCACUUGAGGCCAGGAGUUCAAGACCAGCCUGGCCAACAUGGAGAAACCCCAUCUCUACUAAAAAUACAAAAAUUAGCAGGAUGUGGUGGUGCACGCCUGUAAUCCCAGCUACUCGGGUGGCUGAGGCAGGAGAAUUGCUUGAACCUGGGAGGCGGAGGUUGCAGUAAGCCUAGAUGGUGCCACUGCACUCCAGCCUGGGCAACAAAGUGAGACUCUGUCUCAAAAACAAAAACAAAAACAAACAAACAAACCAAAAAGAGAUUCCAGAGAGGGGAACCCUUGCCUUGCCCCAGCUCAAGGUAGCUGGGAGAAUUCUAAUGGCAUGCCUGGAUCACCUCUGACCAGCACCUCCUUUCUGCUCUUUUAAAAUAUCCCAUGUCAGUGCGAAAGAUGUGACAGGCCUUUCUCCAUCUUCAAGAGUGACACCUCUUCUGAAAUGUUCACCCAAUGCGUGUUCUGCCGGAUAGAUACAAGGGGCUUGCCAGCAGAUACUUCAUCGUCAUCAUCAUCAUCGGAAAGGGAGAACUCACCGCCGCCAAGGGGAAGCAAGGAUGACUGACAGCCACAGGCCCCUUUGAGUGACUCCAGCACAGGCUACCUAGCAUGUAGGUUUCGGGGCUUUGCAGGGGCUUUCUCUUGGGCCCCUCCCAGGCUCAGCAGGCCUGUCAGACUGGGGCAGGACCCAAGCCCUGGCUGGACUCAGCACAGUGCCACCUCCUCAGCUCUCAGCUUGGGGAGUGAACACUUUCCGUUUUCAUGCAGAAUAAAUCUAAUUCCUUUGGAAAA